AUGGAGAGGGACAGGAGGAAACGCAGCGCCAGCAGCAUCUCAUCUACCCUCCUUGACACCUCCCCGUGGCUCCAGCCAGACCCUAGAGGUCAGCCUUGCGGACCAACAGGAGGACUCCCAGCUUUCCCUUUUCAAGAGGUCCCCAGACACCGGCCACCCUCUUCCAGCCCCUGCGGCCAGUGCAAGGAGGCACCAAUGCUCUGAGGCUGUCGCGUGGUGCAGCGUCGAGCAUCCUCGCCGAGGUCCUUUCUGCUGCCUGUCCCGCCUCACCCCGCUCCAUCACACCAGCUGGCCCUCUUUGCUUCCUUUUCCCAGAAUCGUUAAGCCCCGACUCCCACUAGCACCUCGUACCAACCUCGCCCCACCCCAUCCUCCUGCCUUCCCGCGCUCCGGUGUCCCCCGCUGCCAUGAGCUCCCCCAUCAGCAAGAGCCGCUCGCUUGCCGCCUUCCUGCAGCAGCUGCGCAGUCCGAGGCAGCCCCCGAGACUGGUGACAUCUACGGCGUACACGUCCCCUCAGCCGCGAGAGGUGCCAGUCUGCCCGCUGACAGCUGGUGGCGAGACUCAGAACGCGGCCGCCCUGCCGGGCCCCACCAGCUGGCCACUGCUGGGCAGCCUGCUGCAGAUUCUCUGGAAAGGGGGUCUCAAGAAACAGCACGACACCCUGGUGGAGUACCACAAGAAGUAUGGCAAGAUUUUCCGCAUGAAGUUGGGUUCCUUUGAGUCGGUGCACCUGGGCUCGCCAUGCCUGCUGGAAGCGCUGUACCGCACCGAGAGCGCGUACCCGCAGCGGCUGGAGAUCAAACCGUGGAAGGCCUAUCGCGACUACCGCAAAGAAGGCUACGGGCUGCUGAUCCUGGAAGGGGAAGACUGGCAGCGGGUCCGGAGUGCCUUUCAAAAGAAACUAAUGAAACCAGGGGAAGUGAUGAAGCUGGACAACAAAAUCAAUGAGGUCUUGGCCGAUUUUAUGGGCAGAAUAGAUGAGCUCUGUGAUGAAAGAGGCCACGUUGAAGACUUGUACAGCGAACUGAACAAAUGGUCGUUUGAAAGUAUCUGCCUCGUGUUGUAUGAGAAGAGAUUUGGGCUUCUCCAGAAGAAUGCAGGGGAUGAAGCUGUGAACUUCAUCAUGGCCAUCAAAACAAUGAUGAGCACGUUUGGGAGGAUGAUGGUCACUCCAGUCGAGCUGCACAAGAGCCUCAACACCAAGGUCUGGCAGGACCACACUCUGGCCUGGGACACCAUUUUCAAAUCAGUCAAAGCUUGUAUCGACAACCGGUUAGAGAAGUAUUCUCAGCAGCCUAGUGCAGAUUUCCUUUGUGACAUUUAUCACCAGAAUCGGCUUUCAAAGAAAGAAUUGUAUGCUGCUGUCACAGAGCUCCAGCUGGCUGCGGUGGAAACGACAGCAAACAGUCUAAUGUGGAUUCUCUACAAUUUAUCCCGUAAUCCCCAAGUGCAACAAAAGCUUCUUAAGGAAAUUCAAAGUGUAUUACCUGAGAAUCAGGUGCCACGGGCAGAAGAUUUGAGGAAUAUGCCGUAUUUAAAAGCCUGUCUGAAAGAAUCUAUGAGGCUUACGCCGAGUGUACCAUUUACAACUCGGACUCUUGACAAGGCAACAGUUCUGGGUGAAUAUGCUUUACCCAAAGGAAUUGUCCGCAAAUACGACAUCCAGGCCACAGACAAUGAGCCUGUUGAGAUGCUACACUCAGGCACCCUGGUGCCCAGCCGGGAACUCCCCAUCGCGUUUUGCCAGCGAUAAUACGCCUCAGGUGAGCAUCUAGGCGGUUCAUUAUCCUCUGCAAGGUAGUGAGAAUGACGAGGGAUGAGCUAUGCUGGGAAGUCAGCCAGACUGGGGUUUGAAUCCCAGCUCACCUCUAACUUGCUGGGUGACCUUGAGCAGUUCCCUAAACUCUCUACUUCCUUUUUUUUUUUCAUUUGUAAAAUGAUGACCCAAAGAGAGUGUAUCACAAAAAUUUAAUAUGAAUACCAAGUAGUUAUUCCUGAGCCUGGCAUCAAUUAAGUGUUCAGUAAAUGCUAGCAGCUGUUCAUGGUUUUUGCAUGUGAAUAGUAAGGGUUGGCAAACUUUUUCCGUAAAGGGCCAGUUGGCAAAUAUUUUAGGUUUUAUGGACCAUACAGUCUUUGUCACAUCCUCUUAAUACUACCUUGGAACAUGAAAGCAGCCACAGGCAAUUUGUAAACUAAUGAGUGAGCUGAUGUCCUAGCUUUCUAUUGCUGCCACCGCAAAUUACUAAAACUUAGUGAGUUACACGACACACAUCUAUUAUCUUACAGUUCUAUAGGUCAGAAGUCUGAUGAGGCUCUUCCAGGCUAAAAUUAUCGUGUUGUCGGGGCUCUUUCUGGAGGUUCUAGAGGAGGAUCUAUUCUCUUGCUAGUUUGGUUGUUGGCAGAAUUUAGUUCUUCAUGGUUACAGGACUGAAGUCUUUAUUUUUUUGCUGCUGUCAGCUGAAGGCGAUCCUCAACUUUGAGAGAUUUCCCAUAUUCCUUGGCUCAUGAAACCUUCCCCAACUGAAAGCCAGUAACAAUGGUUGGUUGAGUCCCUCUCACACUUUGAAUCUCUCUUUCUUCUUACAUUGCUUCUGUCUGACAAGAUAUUAUCCAGGAUCAUGUCUCCCAUCUCCAAGUUCAUAAAUUUAAUUUCAUCUGGAAAGCCCUUUUUUUCAUAUAAGGUAGUAUAUUCACGUGUUCCAGGGAUUAGGGCAUUCACAUUUUAGGAGAUCUGUUAUUCUGCCUACAAAGGCUGUGUUCUGAUAAAUUUUAUAAAAAACAAGCGGUGGACUGUAUUUAGCCCUAGGGUCUAGGUUUGUGUUAUGCAACCACAUGUAAUAUAAAUGUAUAUAUUUAUCAGCCUGUAUUGAACACAAUAGAAUAUUUUUUCUGCAGUAUGCCAUUCAAUACUUUUUCUGACAAUAGAGGAGUUCUCAUGUUCCCUCCACAACUUUUGCCAUGUCCAUAUACCAACCAGGUGCUAUUUAUUUCAAUACUACUGAGUUAUUUCCUUUAAAUAACAUAAGCCAAAUAGCAUAUGUUGGCCUCGUCCUGAGUAAUAAUUUCCUUAAUGAAAUUAAGAGUUAGUAAGUCUAGUUAUGUUCUCCUAAUAGACAUUACAAUGAAUUCAAAACUAUUGAAGUGAUCAAAAGUUAGCCUAAGAAGGCCCUAAUUUUUUUUUUUUUUUUUUUUUUUGAGACAGUGUCUCACACUGUCACCUGGGCUGGAGUGCAAUGGUGCAAUCUCAGCUCACUGCAACCUCCGCCUCCUGGGUUCAUGCGAUUCUUCUGCCUCAGCCUCCCGAGUAGCUGGGAUUACAGGCAGGUGCACACCACCACACCCAGCUAAUUUUUUGUAUUUUUAGUAGAGAUGGGGUUUCAUUAUGUUGGCCAGACUGGUCUUGAACUCCUGACCUCGUGAUCCACCCGCCUCGGCCUCCCAAAGUGCUGGGAUUGCAAGUGUGAGCCACCACCCCUGGUGGUGGAAAUAAGACAUUUGUAACAUAUGGCUUUAUAGGCUGACAUGUCGGUGUUUAAACCCGGAUUCUAUCAUUGUGUUCUUUUAGCAGCACCUUCUAGGAUUUUCCUAGAAAAAAAUGCUGUUUGCCAAUGGCAAGUUAAGGAGCAUUUGCUUAUUGGUAGAUUAUUUAGAGAAACAUGCAAUUACAGAUGAAAUUUCUGAACAAGGCCCAAAUGAAUACAUUAUUAUUCCUCCACCAAGUGUCUGAUGCUAUUAUGAAAUUUGUCAAAUUCUGAGCAUCCCAACCAACAGAACUGAAUCAAGUAGGGUAAGGAAAGUAUUCUAGCUGCAUUGUGACACCCCAGCCUUCAGCAAAGAGCAUGCAUGUUUAUCACAGUAAGCCACACCUUUUAAGUUUUAGCAUUUUUUCUUUGGCUAAUAAUUUGUCUUGUUUAAAUACACUUCUUUGAUAUACAAUUAGGGUAUACCUUUUUUUUUUUUUUUUUUUUUUUUUUUUUUUUUUUUUUUUUUUUACCAAGACCAAAACAGCCAUUUCAACUUUUCUGCAAGAAUGGUGCUUAUGGCUUCUACGUUACCGGAAAGCAAACUUCAAACACCACACCAUACAACAGCUUAUAAAGAAUAUUUAGGCCCAGGUGUUGAUACUUUUUCUUCUGCAAAAUUGUUCCAGAAGCUGUACUGUCUUUCUAGAUGGUGGUAUUUGCUAACAUCAUAUCCAACUCAGGGAAGCGGACUGAGUGCUGGGAUCCAAGGCAUUCUACAGGGUUCACUGCUGGUUUACACUUCACCUGUGUCAGCACCAUCUUCAGGUGCUUAGAAUGGCCUGGGAGCCUGUUCUGUCUUGCAUCUUCCAUGACAUGAAAGGGAGGCUGGCACUUGUCAGUCAGGUAGAGGUUACAAACCGUUUCAGGCCCUGCCUACCACAUUCACUGUUUGAAUCUUUAAUUCCCAAGAAUAAGUUUACAUUUCACAAUGAAUGACCUACAACAGCUAAAUUUUCUGGGGCUGGGAGUAAUACUGACAAUCCAUUUACUGUAGCUCUGCUUAAUGUACUACUUAGGAAAAUGUCCCUGCUUAAUAAUGUAAGCCAAGCUAAAUGAUGGUUAAAGUUAUCAGGCCUCCCAUGAAAUUGCGUUCUUCCUGCAUUGAAAUAAAAACAUUAUUGGGAAACUAGAGAACACCUCUAUUUUUAAAAGGACUUUAACGAAGUCAAACAACUUAUAAGACUAGUGAUUCACUGGGGCAUUAUUUUGUUAGAGGACCUUAAAAUUGUUUAUUUUUUAAAUGUGAUUCCUUUAUGGCAUUAGGGUAAAGAUGAAGCAAUAAUUUUUAAAUUGUGUAUGUGCAUAUGAAGCACAGACAUGCAUGUGUGUGUGUGUCUGUGUGUGUGUGUCCGUGUAUGUGUGUGUGGGUUCUAAUGGUAAUUUGCCUCAGUCAUUUUUUUAAUAUUUGCAGUACUUGAUUUAGGAUCUGUGGUGCAGGGCAAUGUUUCAAAGUUUAGUCACAGCUUAAAAACAUUCAGUGUGACUUUAAUAUUAUAAAAUGAUUUCCCAUGCCAUAAUUUUUCUGUCUAUUAAAUGGGACAAGUGUAAAGCAUGCAAAAGUUAGAGAUCUGUUAUAUAACAUUUGUUUUGUGAUUUGAACUCCUAGGAAAAAUAUGAUUUCAUAAAUGUAAAAUGCACAGAAAUGCAUGCAAUACUUAUAAGACUUAAAAAUUGUGUUUACAGAUGGUUUAUUUGUGCAUAUUUUUACUACUGCUUUUCCUAAAUGCAUACUGUAUAUAAUUCUGUGUAUUUGAUAAAUAUUUCUUCCUACAUUAUAUUUUUAGAAUAUUUCAGAAAUAUACAUUUAUGUCUUUAUAUUGUAAUAAAUAUGUACAUAUCUAGGUAUAUGCUUUCUCUCUGCUGUGAAAUUAUUUUUAGAAUUAUAAAUUCACGUCUUGUCAGAUUUCAUCUGUAUACCUUCAAAUUCUCUGAAAGUAAAAAUAAAAGUUUUUAAAUAUUUGA